ACUUUCUAGUUAGUUGGCAGAGAGAGAGCACACCAAUGAGUGAGCACAGGCACAUGUGUCUUCUGCUUGGAAUAGCCCUUCUCAGGGCACCUCUGUCUGGAAUGGCCCACGUGUGUUCUGCCUGCUCCGGUCCACUGUGAUCCUGAGACUCUAAGCUCAGCUCCUGGCCCUCUUGGAGUGGCACCACCAUGCCUGGUCCCCAGCCUCCCAGAGCACCCAAGGGGGAAAGCUGUGGUGUCCCUGCUACAAAGCACAGGCUCAGGAACCUGGCUCAGAGCUGCUCCUCAGUGCCAGCUGCUGGACUGGACAAGAUUUUAGGCAAGGCACGGCCACACACCAGGAAGAGCCUGGCAUCCGCAGUGACCCUCGAGCAGCUGUCCCUGCAGCUGGGCCUGCCCCUCAAGCACGCUGAGCCUGUCCUUCACAGCCCCAUGGUGCUGACCCAGGGCCCUGAGACCACCAGGAGGCACCUCUUCCUCUUCAGGGACUGGCUGGUCAUUGCCAAGCAGAGGUCUUCCAAGAGCUACAGAGUCGAACAGAAGCUGCAUCUAUCUGGCGUGCAGGCUGUCACCUGUGACAGAGAGGAAAGGCAGGAUGGGGACAAAGACCAGGAUCUCACUAUCAGUUUAGGAAAUUCUCUGGUCUUCAUGCUGGCUUCUGACCCUUGUGUCGCCGAGUUUCCCUCUUCCGGCCUCUUCUUGAAGCCUCUUCAUCCUCUCCUGACAUCCAUACUCACCUGUGCCCUCCGUUGGCUGGUGGUGCCAUCUGAUCUAGAGACCCACUGGAACAGGGGGCUGUGUGCCCCCCAGGUCAGUACUGAGAGCCUCUGCUGCCCCUUUGUAAAUGCACCUUAGCCGAAAACAGAGAUUCUGACUGAGGAAUUCCAGACAUCUCUGGAGAGACCUCAUAUGUGGAACCUUCUCAGUGUAUUUCAUCAACCGUGUCCUUUCCAGCCUAAAUGGUCUCCCUGACUCAGGCAUUCCCAAACUGAGAAGCUUCAGGGGAUUUGGAAAUAGCCUAGAACCCGAAGCCAAGAAGACCAACAUUGGAAUCCUAAAUCUGUCUUUUCCUGAGUAUUUUACCCAGGCAAAUUUCAUUCAGUAUCCUCAUCCAUUAAGGAAGUAGCUUUAUCUGCACUACAGAAUUUUGAGGAAGAAUAAAUGAGCUGCUGUCACACAUAGUUUAGAGAACUAAGAAUGAGGUAGCUUAAAUAGAAAUAACUAACACAGAAUUUCUCGCACUUAGCAGGUGUGUGAUGCAAGUGCUGGCUGCUAACUGGUUUUUUGUUUUGGUUGGGGGAAGGAAGAUCCAGGCCAGUGAAGAUGGUCUUCACAGCCAAGAUGAUUGAUAAGGUUAGAAUUACUAAGUUUCUGAUCUCAGUCCAUCUCUGAGGGGUGACUUGGGAACUCUCCCACAACCUCCCUAUUUGCUUCAAAUUGUUCUGGCAAACUGCUUAAUGGCAAAGUGUGGAGAAGGGCUUUCUACUGGAGAGCAGAUAUAAACACCUGCAAAAGGAGGGGCCAUGAAGAAGGCUCACUCUGCAGCCUUACAGAGGCCCAAAUGAUAGCAGAGAAGCUUGCAGCCACACGUAAGAACUGAGAGGUUCACUGAGCAUCACAAUAAAAAACCAGCUCCGCAAAGUUCGUAGCCACAGAUGUAGGGCUUUGGCAGGAAAUGGUUGGGGUUGUGUCAUCUUCUUUUACUUUCUGAAAUAUUCUAGAAAAAUGGCUUCUGUUUUAUCCUUGCAGUAGAUAACUGUGGUCCUAUAAACUUCAUAGGAUCAGCUCAUAGUGUACAAGGUAGGAACCAUCAUUAAUGUUUGUGACACUCUUUCUUGACAGAGAAACUUUAGAAUACUAAUAAUAAUAAUGGUCCACAGUUACCCAGAACUCGCUAUGCGCCUGUCACUCUUCUGAGCACUUGAUAUACAAUAAGUCACCCACUUCCUUUCUGACACAGAUGUCCUAGUCACAUGUGAGGUAAGAGUCUUUCAAACUGGGCGUCACAAAUGGAUUUUCUCCUUGCAGAAUGGCUUCCUCCAAGUUAGAAAAAAUUCUUUCUCUUACUAAUGUGGGAAGUUCCACCCCCUCUAAUAUCAGAUGACCACAAGAAGCCCUGGCAUCUCCACUCACGCUGGCCUGAGCAUGGCUAUGCCCUUUGAACUGUCCCUCCCGUUGUAGUCUCUGGGAUAUCAUGCAAUCCUGUGACUGCUGUUUUUGAUUCAUUCAGAUGGGUUCGUUUACAAUGUCAGCACAGGCCAACCAGCAUAGACAACGCUUCUUUUCAUAAAAAGGAACUUCAGAUACUGUGUUUUUAAGAGAAUUAAAUGAGAUAAUUCAGGUAAACCUCUGAGCAUGGCGCCUGCCCCCAGGGAAGGGUUUGGAUGGUUUGAGAACUACUAGAGUGGUCGCCUGCGAGGGCUGCCAUUACAAGGGACCACAGACUGGGUGGGUUAAAUGGCAGAAAUGUACAUCUCCUGGUUCUGGAGGCUGGAAGUCCAAGAUCAAGGUGU